GUUAUGCUCUGGGCCAUUCCUGAGCUCGGGUCACCCUGCCCCAUCUCCAUCUCCUAUGAGAUGAGUGACUCCCAAGACCCCACCACUUCCCCUGUAGUUACCACCCAGGUAGAGCUGGGGGGCUGCAGCCGGCAAGGUGGGGGCAAUGGGUUCCUCCGUUUUCGCCAGCACCAGGAGGUCCAGGCCUUCCUCAGCCUUCUGGAGGACAGUUUUGUCCAGGAAUUCCUCUCCAAAGACCCCUGCUUCCAGAUUUCAGAUAAGUAUCUCCUGGCCAUGGUGCUGGUCUACUUCCAGCGCGCCCACCUGAAGCUCAGCGAGUAUACCCACAGCAGCCUGUUCUUGGCCCUGUACCUUGCAAACGACAUGGAGGAGGACCUGGAGGGCCCCAAAUGUGAGAUUUUUCCAUGGGCCCUGGGAAAAGAUUGGUGUUUACGAGUGGGGAAAUUCCUGCACCAGAGGGAUAAGCUUUGGGCACGGAUGGGUUUCCGGGCUGUUGUGAGCCGCCAGUGCUGUGAGGAGGUCAUGGCAAAGGAGCCAUUCCACUGGGCUUGGACUCGGGACCGGCGCCCCCACCAUGGUGGGGUUCAGAGGGUCUGUCCACAGGUCCCUGUUCGCCUUCCCCGGGGCCCUGGCCUCUCGCCGCCCCACUGUUCCCCCUGUGGUUUGCCCCAGCACUGCAGCAGCCACUUGCUUAAGCCUGUGUCAUCCAAGUGCCCUUCUCUGACCUCUGAAUGUCAUCGCCCUCCCUCCCAAAAUUAUCUCUCAAGGGUCAAAAACGCCUGGGGUGGGGACUUUCUCAUCGUCUUGCCUCCCCAGAUGCAACUGGAACCAGGCACCUACUCCCUCCGCAUCUUCCCAAAGCCUCCGGCACGCCCUGGGCACUGAAGCUCUGCAGGGUGAAGAACAGCACGCCUGCUGGCCCACUGACUGACACACCAUUGGCUGUGCUCCCACCCCUGCCCCUUCCUCCCAGCCUGCAGCUUGUGCCCACUCUGGUGCCAGUCCCCUCUAAUAAAUUCAUGUCCACAGGACACCAACUGUG